UGUUGAAGGUCACAGUUUUCUCCUCGGCACUGACUGGGCCCUCUCUGACAGUAGCUUGUACUUAGAAUAAAUAAUCAGCUGAAAUGAAUGAAUGAAUGAAAAAAGAAUAUUUGUGGUUUUCAUUCAAAGUAGAAAAGUGAUGCUAUCAACAUUUUUUCCCCCUUGUGAAGGCACUGGAUUGAUCUAUGAUGGUGGAAUGCAAGAAGUACAUGUUCUACCAUCAGCAAACAGUUGACCCCCACCUCUGCUAGCAACUGGCGAUGGACUAGGUCCUACUGAUGUUGGCUAUCUUGCCUCCUGGUUGCUUGACUCCAGGAUCACAGAACAAUGACAAAAGACAAUUUCUGCUGGAGCGACUGCUGGAUGCAGUGAAACAGUGCCAGAUCCGCUUUGGAGGGAGAAAGGAGAUUGCCUCGGAUUCCGACAGCAGGGUCACCUGUCUGUGUGCCCAGUUUGAAGCCGUCCUGCAGCAUGGCUUGAAGAGGAGUCGAGGAUUGGCACUCACAGCGGCAGCGAUCAAGCAGGCAGCGGGCUUUGCCAGCAAAACCGAAACAGAGCCCGUGUUCUGGUACUACGUGAAGGAGGUCCUCAACAAGCACGAGCUGCAGCGCUUCUACUCCCUGCGCCACAUCGCCUCAGACGUGGGCCGGGGUCGCGCCUGGCUGCGCUGUGCCCUCAACGAACACUCCCUGGAGCGCUACCUGCACAUGCUCCUGGCCGACCGCUGCAGGCUGAGCACUUUUUAUGAAGACUGGUCUUUUGUGAUGGAUGAAGAAAGGUCCAGUAUGCUUCCUACCAUGGCAGCAGGUCUGAACUCCAUACUCUUUGCGAUUAACAUCGACAACAAGGAUUUGAACGGGCAGAGUAAGUUUGCUCCCACCGUUUCAGACCUCUUAAAGGAGUCAACGCAGAACGUGACCUCCUUGCUGAAGGAGUCCACGCAAGGAGUGAGCAGCCUGUUCAGGGAGAUCACAGCCUCCUCUGCCGUCUCCAUCCUCAUCAAACCUGAACAGGAGACCGACCCCUUGCCUGUCGUGUCCAGGAAUGUCAGUGCUGAUGCCAAAUGCAAAAAGGAGCGGAAGAAGAAAAAGAAAGUGACCAACAUAAUCUCAUUUGAUGAUGAGGAAGAUGAGCAGAACUCUGGGGACGUGUUUAAAAAGACACCUGGGGCAGGGGAGAGCUCAGAGGACAACUCCGACCGCUCCUCUGUCAAUAUCAUGUCCGCCUUUGAAAGCCCCUUCGGGCCUAACUCCAAUGGAAGUCAGAGCAGCAACUCAUGGAAAAUUGAUUCCCUGUCUUUGAACGGGGAGUUUGGGUACCAGAAGCUUGAUGUGAAAAGCAUCGAUGAUGAAGAUGUGGAUGAAAACGAAGAUGACGUGUAUGGAAACUCAUCAGGAAGGAAGCACAGGGGCCACUCGGAGUCGCCCGAGAAGCCACUGGAAGGGAACACCUGCCUCUCCCAGAUGCACAGCUGGGCUCCGCUGAAGGUGCUGCACAAUGACUCCGACAUCCUCUUCCCUGUCAGUGGCGUGGGCUCCUACAGCCCAGCAGAUGCCCCCCUCGGAAGCCUGGAGAACGGGACAGGACCAGAGGACCACGUUCUCCCAGAUCCUGGACUUCGGUACAGUGUGGAAGCCAGCUCUCCAGGCCACGGAAGUCCUCUGAGCAGCCUGUUACCUUCUGCCUCAGUGCCAGAGUCCAUGACAAUUAGUGAACUGCGCCAGGCCACUGUGGCCAUGAUGAACAGGAAGGAUGAGCUGGAGGAGGAGAACAGAUCACUGCGAAACCUGCUCGACGGUGAGAUGGAGCACUCAGCCGCGCUCCGGCAAGAGGUGGACACCUUGAAAAGGAAGGUGGCUGAACAGGAGGAGCGGCAGGGCAUGAAGGUCCAGGCGCUGGCCAGAGAGAACGAGGUGCUCAAAGUCCAACUGAAGAAAUAUGUAGGAGCUGUCCAGAUGCUGAAAAGAGAAGGUCAAACAGCUGAAGUGCCAAAUCUUUGGAGUGUUGAUGGAGAAGUUACAGUAGCUGAACAGAAGCCGGGAGAAAUUGCUGAAGAACUCGCAAGCUCCUACGAAAGAAAGCUCAUCGAGGUGGCAGAGAUGCAUGGCGAGCUGAUUGAGUUCAACGAGCGCCUGCACAGGGCCCUGGUAGCCAAGGAAGCCCUCGUGUCCCAGAUGAGGCAGGAGCUCAUCGAUCUCCGGGGACCGGUGCCUGGAGAUUUGAGUCAAACGUCCGAAGACCAGAGUUUGUCGGAUUUUGAAAUAUCAAACCGGGCGCUGAUCAACGUCUGGAUCCCCUCAGUGUUUCUCCGGGGCAAAGCAGCAAAUGCAUUCCACGUGUAUCAGGUCUACAUCCGGAUAAAAGACGAUGAAUGGAAUAUUUAUCGCCGGUAUACAGAGUUCAGGAGUUUGCACCACAAGUUACAAAACAAGUACCCUCAAGUGAGGGCCUACAACUUCCCACCCAAAAAGGCCAUUGGAAACAAGCCGCCACCAUCUCCUGCCUGGAUGACUGCAGCAGCAUCCUUGCUGGCCUCUCUGCUUCCUGCAUUGCCUCCUCUGAAUCUUCAGGUGACCUCCGAAGUCACCUCCUCCCAGGAUGCCAAGUUUGUGGAGGAACGGAGAAAGCAGCUCCAGAAUUACCUGCGCAGCGUCAUGAACAAAGUCAUCCAGAUGGUCCCCGAGUUCGCUGCCAGCCCCAAGAAGGAGACCCUCAUCCAGCUGAUGCCCUUCUUCGUUACCUCGUGGUGUUGGGAUCCGGAGAACCAGACCCAGACCUGCCUUCAAGGAACCCUUGGGUACUGCCAGAGCCAUUUCUGGAUCAGUUGUGGAUGGUGGAAGUCUUGGAGACCCAUUUCAAACCAAGAGGUAGGAGGUAAAGGCCUUGAUGGAUGUCAGCAUAGUUCACAGUGGAAUUAGAUUUCACGGGGCACCCAUCACGCAGUCCUGAGGCCCAGGUGUUGCCUAGGAAUGAAUUCAAAGGCUAUUCAGCCUGGCAUGCUCUGAUACUGCCCAUCAGGACCCCCGCAGCCAUGCAGUACAGAAGGCAGAGCAAGGCCACUCCCUCCCACUCCACAGAUCCAAGGGGCUAAGACACAGGGAGAACAUUCUCCAUGAUCUUCACAUCCUGGAGGCAGAACUGGGUUUUCAAAGUGGUGAGACUCACAGACUUAUGAGGGAGCUAGGUCGUGGAAGAUGCUGGCCACAUCCCCGCCACACACACAGAUCAGUCCUAGCUGGGUUGCAGGGAUCCAGCCCUCUAAGCUUCAAAGGCAGCUCCUAGUAAGUGGAGUAUUGACCGGCUCGCCAGACCCAGAUCACAGGUGAAACAAAGUGAAAAGUUAGUCUCUCCUCGCAGCCAUUUUCACUGAUGAGCAGUUGAGGCUGUCCGAUUAAUGUCAGCCGCAUGCUGGUGACAGGACACAACGCAGUGUACCCCAAGAGGCUUAUUAAAAAGAACAGCCACUCCUGGGGCCCUCUGAGGGUGCCCUCACACACAGACCCCCUUUUCCCCAACUCCCCAGUGCUGUGUUAAGUUGCUAGCAGCAGGGAGGAUGGAGAUGGAGUUUCUGAAAUGAACACCAAAGCACAUGUCAGGACCACGCGUGGCCUGGCAGGGGGCUCAUUACCGCAGCUUACAUCCUUCUCCCUGCAGGGGAGGGGAGGCAGUGCCCUGGGGACUUAUGGGCUGUCUCCUAGGUGACCGUGGCAUCCCAGGAGUUCCUUCUCCAGUUGCCUUCCAGGUGAGCUUAGAGCCAGGUGCAUCCCUGGGGGCAUGAUGUCCCCAGAGUGUCUACCAGCUUGGUGACAAUGGACCCUGCAACCCAGGAGGCCUGGCCCCUCAUGGAUUUAGGGAUGGAAUCAUCUGUGCCGUUUUCCUUCCCGUGUUUUCUGCCCAGUAGUUUGAACCGCAUUUCUAAGGCCGUUCACUCUCCUGUGUGACCCCAAAAUGGCUCUGGCAAUACCAGGUCUGUGGAGUAAGAUUGAGGUCUGACCUGAGCAUAGGGUUCACAGAGGAGUGAACCCUGCUGGAGGUGGCCAAGUUCAGAAGUGAAGGGCGAGGGCAUUCACUAAGCAGCAUCCCCAUGGGCCACGCUCUAUCCCAGCAUCAAACGUUAUCGUUGGCUUUGUCCCAAGAACCUGCAGGGCAGAUUCUGUGAUUUCCCCCUUUAUUUUUGCUUGCACCAUUUUUUAAAACAGCUCAAGAGACAGAUCACAUACCAUACAAUUUACCCACUUAAAGUGCACACAGCUUGCUAGUUUGACUUUGAUCCCCCUUCAUAGGCUAGGAACUCGAGUCCUAGAAAGGAGCAUCGUGAGCAGCCCAAGUACACCUGCUGGUGAAUGACACAGCCAGGAGUCAUCUAAGACACUGUCCCCGUGGUCCCUAGUUUUUACCCAGAGACGGGGACAAAGGUCGCUGGCUCUUGAGAGCUACAGGCUAUCAGGGUCUUCCCUGAGGGGCUGUUUUAUGUCGGGAAAGUCUAGAUUUACAGGCACUGCCUUCUUUGGAGUCGAGAUUGAAGCCUACCGUGGUACUGUUUCUCGCUUUUAUGGCAUAGUUCCUUGAGUUUUCACAAAGGCUUGGAGUCCUUUAGCCAUCACCAUCAAGAUGUGGAACAACUCCUUUCCCCCCAAAUUUCCUAGCAUUCCCCUAUAGGCAACCCGACAGCUCCCGGUCUGUGCUUUGUCAUUUCUAGUUUUGGGAAUUUGACGAUGUGCUUGAGAUUCGUCCAUGUUGCCAAAAACCUGCAUAGUAAGAAGCAAACAUUCACCCAACACAAGGGGUGAGGGCUGAUGCGUAAGAAAAACUGCUUCAAUGCGCCUUUCAAACCGUGUUUACAUCAUUGCAAGGGCCAAGGUCACCUCGAAAUGUAGGUACUGGAAGAGAAAUCCAGAAUGUUACAUAGAAGACGCACGCUAACAACAGAGCCUAGGAAAGGUCGCCACACGUCCUCAUCCCAGCUCCAGGGGGGGCAACUCUGGGCUCAGGGAUGUCACUUCCCACAGUCAACAUGCUGGGAUUGAGGCUCAUACCCUGAAAGUGGCCUCCCCAUCAUCACUGACCCCGCCCAGGUAGCAGAGGAACGUCGGGUUCUGGAUCCACAGCUCGGAAAGUCUGCUUUGUGACUGGAGAGAGUCACCGUCGAGGAGUGGCCAUUAUCCUGAGCCUGUCUUUUAUCGCCACGUUGAUAUUUUACCCGUAACCAUGAAAAUAGAUGGCGACUGGAUUUUGUUCCUUGCGGUAUGUCCUUUGCAGGUAAAUUUAGGAAACCUAAUAGGGUAAAAGGCUCAAGGAAUAGGGCUAUUAAAACGGGGAGACUCCUCCCCGCAUGUGAAAAAUUGAGUUGUCUCCCACCACUACCUGAGGGGUCUACCCCACCCCUUUGGGUGGUGGCUUAGGCCUCCAUGUCUGUAUCACCACAUCUCACAGACGAGACUGUCCUGGCCCCAGAAGGUAGGAACUGAGUCUUUUCAAUUCCCCGAGAGCCCAUGAUGGGGUCUGGCCUCAUGUAAGAGGAACAUGAGGAAAGCCAGAGAUGGCACUGUCAUUCUUUACCCAACAGCCACAACUUCUCCACCCUUGUCUGCCGACCUGUCUGAAGACUGCAACACCCACCCAUUUGCUGCUUUUUAUUUAUUCAGGCUGCCUGUAAAUAUCCCUGCUGAAUAGCCAUCUCUCCCCAUCUCUAGCCCCUUGGGCCUCUGCCGUCUCUGGAGCAGGCAGCCGAAGACCUACAAUACCUAGACGCUGAUCUUGUUCAAGAAAGACGAGGAAGGGCUUUUCAGAUAAGGUUCCCUCUGCCCCUGCAGCACCCUCUUCCCCCAGGGUAGGGAGUUGAGGAGUUGCACCGGUAAAAGGUUGUGGUUUGGCAACGAUGCUGUAUUUUGGGAGUUUGUAAUAUCUUUGUAAAAUCCUCCUUGAUUGGGUGUGGUGGAUCGUGCCUAUAAUCCCAGCACUUGGGAGGCCUGAGGUAGAGGAUUGCUUGAGUUCAGGAGUUUGAGACCGUCCUGGGCACCAUAGGGAGACCCCCACAUCUCUAAGAGAAAAAAAUCUCUACUCAGUUCCUUUGGUAUAUUAGAUGCCUCUACCAGUAAAAGUUCCUAUGAAGUUGCUGGCUAGACUUCACUAGUGUCUCUUACCUUAUUUCAGUCAUUUCAGGAUGUCAAAGGAGCCAAAUCUAUUUCUAAUCACCACCAACUGCAUAAAUAUGCAUCAAUGAUGUAUGAUUGGCACUAUUAUCCUCAUUUCACAGAUCAGAAAGCUGUGUUUUGGGGAGGUUAUGGAUCUUUCUCCAAGGUCUAGAGUGUCUUAACAGAAGGAACUCAAGUUUUCUGACUCUGAAUAUGGAGUUAAGGCCUUUGGCAACCCAUUCUUAUGGAUUGCCAUCCAGACGCCCCUUUUUCUUGUUUGUGAAACUGUAACAGACCUAGUCCCAGCAUUAACAGAGUCCCUGCUGGGGAGCAGGAAUGGAACAUAUCUUGUCCACACAUUCCUCUGUUGCUUAGGCCCCAGAGCUGCAAGCCCACUUUGUUAUAAAAAUGCAGUUGUGCCUAACAACUGUCUGCUUCUUGGUGAUUGGCUUUAUGAUUGCAGCCAGCUAAGAAAUGGUGUUGUCAUUCCAGAAGUCUCGGUGGUACACAACGCUGAAGUCGGCAGCUAACAAGGGCUAUGAGAGAUGAGAAUUUCACUCUGAGGAUCCUGUGGGGAGGAGGCAUCUGCAGCAGGGACUGGAGGGAACCUUGGUGUUAAAAAAAAAAAAAAAAAGGCUGUCAUUGUAAAUGUGAGGCGUUUCAGCUUCCGACUACAGCCCAUGUCUCUACUGUUGGACGCCAGUCCUGGGAUGAGCCUGGCACUGGCUUCAUUCCCCUGUAGCAAAGGGGCCCAGUGGGGACACAUGGGGUCGUCUUCUCUUCUGAGUACUGGCCCUAGUCUCUUAUCCACAUUAGCCCCCACUUCCUUUGCCAGUUUACAUACUCCCAGUCCUACCCAACCCCCCACCUUCAGAUUCUGCUAUUCAGCCAGACAGCAUUACCAGUAUUAGGCUGUUCUCAAUCUAUAAAGAUGGCAGUUGCAAGAGGUUCAGCCUCACAUACGCCAGCAGCCACCAGCACUCUCCAUUCAAGUCCACUGUGCUCAGCAGUCUGGGUUUUCCAUCUGUCACGCACUCACUGAAGCCCCUGGUCUAGCCAGAUUUCCGCAGGUGUCAUCCACUCAACUUGUCCCAAAUGAAGCCCAUCCUCCCGUGGCCUCACCUGCCCCCUCCUCAUCCUGGGUUCUCUCAAACCAUCACAGCACCCCUGCCUCCAAGCCUGUGUCCCGAGACAUGGCUCUGCUCCACAUGGCCUCGAGGAUUGAACCAUCCCUGUGUCACAGAAGCCUACUGUCACACCCUCAACCACAGCAGCCUACACUCACUGGGACUUCCCAGGUGCCAGGCACAGACAUGUGACACAUAUAGCCUCGUGACAGCUCAGUGCACGUCCCGAGCUAACCCUGCCUUCCAGGAAGGGGAAGCAGCUGGGCCGGGUCUGCCCGGCUACAAGUCCACCCCCUCCCCAUGGGCCUGCCACCUUCACCUUUUUUCAUUUUCACAUCUAGAGGGCCCUUUACACAGCAACCCUCAGCUCACUUCUGGUCACCCUCCACACCUCUGCCUCCUCCGGGAAGCCCUCUGUGCCCUGCUCAGAACAACCUGAGUUCCCUCUCAUUGGGGCAUCCACCGUGAUCCACCACAGCCAUCUGUCCAGUGUCUGCCCUCCCCAUCCUCAAUGACACUGUGGCUUUCCAAACCUGAGACCACUUCUGCACCCCUUCAUGCCCAGCCCAGCAUGGUGGUGACACAGGUCAUGUGUUUGAAUGUUCACUGUUGCCCAUUGUCUCUCUAGGCACUUGAUCCCCAUGAUGCUUAAAACCACCCCACCUUUAUUCUGUCCAAGGCUCAGAGGGCAGGCAUUUGCCUACAGAAACACAGCUAGUUGGUGGCUUUAGGUAGCCCUUGAAUCCUUACCACCACAGUACUAGGAUAUGCUUAUGGUUGUCAUCCCCAAAUGACAGACAAGGAAACCAAGGGUCAGACAGCACUGCCCACAGCAGGACUGGACAGAGACACGUGCCUCCAAGCUAUGUCCUCUCCCUACCCCUUCAUAACAGUCACCCCACCGACUGCUACCUCUCCUCUCCCAACCAACAAGGCACUGGCCUCUCCCAGGCACUCUCAGAGCCUGUUACCUCCAGGGCCUCUCCCCCCAAGCUCUGGUCAUUGCAGGGCAGGGCUCAUCCUGGCUGUGCUGAAUGAUGAUGGUGGUUGCAGGCUAAGUGGCUGCUCAGACCCCGCAUCUGAAGAGCAUGACAGGAGGGGGUUGUGAGGGCAUGGCUUUAAACUGACUUUUACAUCCAAGCCUUCCUGUAUCUAAGAAUCAGUUCCCCUACACUGCAAGCAAAGACCUCCUUCCAGCAUCUUUGAACCAUCCUCUAAGGAGCAUUCAGGGAUAAAGAGGCUCUUCGUAAGUGGGGUCCCCCAUCCUUUGAAGAGAGGAUCAUGUUUGCUUUGGGCCUGCAGCCAGACACCCACCUAAAGGAGGAAAGCACAGCACACGCCAGGCUGGUUGGGCUCAGAGAUGAUUCAGAGCAGCUCCGGCUUUGUUCAAGGUCAAAUGUUUCUUUUUCAUCCAUGCACAGAAGGCAAAGCAACAACUUGACUUACAGGAAAAGACAAUCAUUAAAAGGGGUCUUCAUUUUGUUAGCUUAUCAGGGUGUCAAACUUGAAACGAGGGAUCUCACUCGCACAGUGGCCAUGUCCCUGGAAAGGUGCAACGCAAAGUAGAUCAUUGUGAAGAGAUUCACUCCUGAGAUACAUGAAGAUGCUAGGCUGUUUCAGGGAACCCUGCAGGGAUCCUCGAGGGGAAUGAUUUCUUUAUGAAUGCAAGUCUCUUAACUCACAUGAUUUGUGAAACUGGGCUUGGAUACAGCUGGGGGUGGAUGUUCCUGAUCUGACAUUCUCACUUGGCAUCUUUGGUCCUUUCUAAACCACAGAUAAGGCAGAGCUAGCUGUGGACACAGUCCUGUCUUCCCUUGUAGGGUCCAGUGGAUCCAGGACUUACAUCCAGCAAGCCACAGCAGCACAGAGGUGCUGCGGACGCAGGAGUGGACAUGGAUCCUGUUAGGUUUUUGCCUUGUUUUAAAACAUUUUAUCCCAGUGAGGUAUUUACUUCCUAUUCAAAUAGCGUAUAGUAGGCAGAGUAAGAACAUUCCUAGCCCCAGAAUUUAUGUGUCCCCUUAUCUAGCAAAAGGGACUUUACAGAUGUGAUUAAGGAUUGGCCAGGCACAGUGGCUCACACCUGUAAUCCCAGCACUUUAGGAGGCUGAGCAAGAGGAUCACUUGAGACCAGCCUGGACAAGAGCAAGACCCCAUCUCUACAAAAAAUUACACUCAGGUAUGGUGGCUAGUACCUAUAGUCCCAGCUGCUCAGGAGGCUGAGGUGAGAGGAUCACUUGAGCCCAGGAGAUCGAGGCUGCAGCAAGUUAUCAUUACACGAUUGCACUGUAAAACCUGGGCAAGAGUCGAGACUGUCUCCAGAAAAUACAAUUUUGAAAAAAUGCAACCACAUCACAGGACUUCCUGCUGAGCACCCUCUGCUCUCACGGUGAAGCCUCCCAGCCUCUACCCUAUCCCCUAAAAAAUGUGCCGAGGGCCUCCCACACAACCCAGACCCAUGCCCUGGGACCCACACACGCUGUGUGUUCGCGUUGCUUCAGAACCAGGAUCAGUGUCCCCCUCUUGGUGUUAUCUUCCACUGUUCCUGGCUCUUAAACACAAUACCAUGCCAAACAACCUUUUAACUAGCCCCUAGCCUAGGGCCUGAUUAUUUUCUUAGGAUUAAUUCCACAGGAAGUCCGUCUCCUGUGUUUUGCUACGCAUCUUGUGUGGCUUUAUGUAGUGUUCUCCAAAGUUGCCUUGGACUUAGAAGCGUACCUUUGCUGGAAAAUCAAGGAAAAUGUGGGGAAGAAAGCUGUGCCUAGAACAUUCUUUCAUAGCCUUAAAAUGUAGACCGGAACGGUGGUACCAUGAGCUAGCUCAGACUCACAGCCAAGCUUGGUUGGAGCCUCGGAGUGCUGU